GGAUGUUUACGGCGGCCGAGGUUGGAGCGGCGCUGCUCGGCCGCGGACACACGAGGGACGCGCCCGAGGAGCUGCAGGUGGCAGCCCAGGCGGUCCGAACCCGUCGGCCGGCCGAGCCUGGAGUAUUGCCUAAGUGUAAUCUUGAACAUGGGCGGUGCUGUGAGUGCUGGUGAAGACAAUGAUGAGCUGAUAGAUAAUUUGAAAGAAGCACAGUAUAUCCGGACUGAGCUGGUAGAGCAGGCUUUCAGAGCUAUCGAUCGUGCAGACUAUUAUCUUGAAGAAUUUAAAGAAAAUGCUUAUAAAGACUUGGCAUGGAAGCAUGGAAACAUUCACCUCUCAGCCCCGUGCAUCUACUCGGAGGUGAUGGAAGCCCUAGAUCUGCAGCCUGGACUCUCGUUUCUGAACCUGGGCAGUGGCACUGGGUAUCUCAGCUCCAUGGUGGGCCUCAUUCUAGGUCCUUUUGGUGUGAACCAUGGGGUGGAACUUCACUCAGAUGUGAUAGAGUAUGCAAAGCAGAAACUGGACUUCUUCAUCAGAACAAGUGAUAGUUUUGACAAGUUUGACUUCUGUGAACCUUCCUUUGUUACUGGGAAUUGCCUGGAGAUUUCUCCGGAUUGUUCUCAGUAUGAUCGUGUAUACUGUGGGGCUGGCGUGCAGAAAGAGCAUGAAGAGUACAUGAAGAAUCUUCUCAAAGUGGGAGGGAUCCUUGUCAUGCCACUGGAAGAGAAGUUGACUAAGAUAACACGCACAGGUCCUUCAGCUUGGGAAACCAAAAAGAUUCUUGCUGUUUCUUUUGCUCCUCUGAUCCAGCCCUGCCAUUCAGAGUCAGGAAAAUCAAGACUUGUCCAGUUACCACCAGUGGCAGUUCGCAGCCUCCAGGACUUGGCUCGCAUCGCCAUCCGGGGCACCAUUAAAAAGAUUAUUCAUCAGGAAACUGUGAGCAAAAACGGAAACGGACUAAAGAACACCCCCAGGUUUAAACGAAGGAGAGUUCGCCGCCGUCGAAUGGAAACGAUUGUCUUUUUGGACAAAGAAGUCUUUGCCAGUCGGAUUUCCAACCCCUCAGAUGACAACAGCUGUGAAGACUUGGAAGAGGAACGGAGGGAAGAAGAAGAGAAGACCCCGCCGGAAACAAAGCCAGACCCCCCAGUGAACUUCCUACGCCAGAAGGUCCUGAGCCUCCCUCUGCCAGAUCCCCUGAAAUACUACUUGCUUUAUUACAGAGAAAAAUAAGUCUCCUGUUUGAAAGGGGGAAAUAGGAAGAGCAGAUUGCUGAGUGUGAAGUUCGUGCUGCCUGUGUGCUGUUGAAGGGUCACCUGGAGGCAGACGUUGUGGGGAAGGGAACUGCUGGGCUCAUCCACACCAUGGUUUUCUUCUAGUUCCUGAUUGACCUCUAAAAUUCUAUUCAGUUGUAUGAUUUGUUUACAUAGUUCCACAAGACCUUCAUUGCAUAGAAGAUUGUUUUCCCAAAGUGGAGAGAAUCUUCAUAGAGAAAAAGAGAAGGCUGUUUCUUUUUCGGCUCUGACGAAACACUGAAGUCUGCGUAAGAGAGACUGUUUGAUGACCGUCCCUCAUGCAACAUGCACGGUACUCACUAAAAAUGAAAACUGAAGUGGAAACUAACCUGUGUUGCUUAUAAAGUGUGAAAGCACAAGCUUAUAAAUGUAUAAAAUCUUUUCUGGGUGUGACGCACCUGCGUCCAAGUUUGAAUUUUUAUGAUAUGUACCACUUAAUUACUGGCACUGAGUAUCACUGAAUUUCUUAGUUUUCUAGUGGGGAAACAUUAUUGAGAAGCCCUCCCUUAUUUUAAGUAAGUUGAUUAAAUCUUAUGUGAGUUGCCAGUUGUAAUUUUUCAAAGGAAAAAUUUUGAUGGGGUGGAGGAAUGAAUUGCCAGAUAAUCUUUCUGGAAUUCCGAGAGAAUUCCAAAGAGGGUUUUUUUUUUUUUUUUUAGGACAUCUUUUGAUACCUUUAAAAGAACCACUGUCAAGUAAUCCUUAAAAGAAUAUCUUGGAAAAGGAAACAGAUUUUUUCCUGUGUGUAAGCAAUAAGUGAAGUUACAUUUGCCCUAACCCUAGGGAUGAUUCUUUACCCAGUUUUAAAGCCCAUCAUGGUAUUCUAAGGUGUUGACACCCUCCAUCCUCAGAGCAGGUCGAAAAUAUUAAAUAGACUGGGGACUCUAUGAUGGGCAGCCUGUGCUUUUUGACUUCAGUUUGCUAUUUUUCUGUGAUCACAUUAGUACUGAUUCAUAGAUUCUAUCUUUUAUAAUUCUGGAGAAAAAGAUUUGUUAGUUUUGUAAUUUUUUUGUAAGACCAAAUGUAUGUAUUUUAGUAGCUCCAUUGCAUGAGAAGAGUGUAACUCACACUGACUUGUGAUAUCAGCCUUCUCUGGGCCUUGUGUGUGGAGAGCUUUCUAUCUUACCAAGUGGUAGGGCUAAAAGAACAACAGCCUUUUUGGUAGUCACAUAGCAGAAUGAUCAGAGUUACAUUGCUUAUUCCAAAACAUUGGUUCUUUUUAAAACAUUUUUUUUUACCCAAAGAAAAGAAUAAUAGAAAUUACUAACAAUAAAUAUAAAUUCAGAGUGUUGAUAUAGGAUUCAGUAUCCAGAGUUUAUUUUUAAUCUUAAUCCUCAGCUUCUUGGGAGUUGCUGGGCUUCAGUGUCUCUGUGGUUUCACCAGCUUAGCUUGAGCUCUGGUUAUUUUGGAUCUUUUCUGCUUUUUUUAAGUAACUGAGUCAUUUUUACCACACAGUCCAGUUUGCAUGUAUAGCUAGGAAACAUGUAUUGCUCUAGAUUGGGCAGUUUAAGUCAUUUUAAAGAAAGUUAGUUCAUAGUUGUUGCCUUUUAACUCAUAGUCAAGCUUCAGUCUUUCAAAGAGAAAUGUGUGAUUUUCAUUUACUUGCUGAUAUUUUGUAGUUUGGAGAUCCUUGUGGGCAUUAUUCUAACUGAUACGUAGACACUUACUUGGAAAUUUUUGGACAUUAUAUUAAAUGAGUGCUAUCUGUGAAAUUGGUUAUAUUAGGUGGCUUGACUAAUGUUUUUUCUAUAAUUGUAUAUGGACUGCAUUUUUAAAAAAACCGCAUUUGCCUUUAUGCUAGAUUGUAAAAAAUUAUAUUAGAAUGCAUAAGACAUGUUUUUCCUUCAUAUGCUAGACUUUUCCUAGCAUUUCGUAUUUCUGUGUUGUCAGUGUGUGAUUUUUAAACCGGAAUUUGGUUUAAAAAAAAUCUGGUGGUAAUAUAUGUGAGAAAUACUUUGGUGUUUACCUUAUGAAAAUAAAGGAUUGUAAGUAAAGUUUCCUGCGCACCUUAUACCAGAAUUCAGUAUAAUACACUACUUUCUGUUUUCAAACAGAUAAAUCAUAAUAUAGUCUGUAUUAUCUGUAAGAUCUGUCUUGUAAACCACAUUCUUGACAACUAUUUGCUUUUGAGUAGUUUGUAUUUUAAUAUGUGACUUUUGUCUUGAAAAGUAGUAAAGCCAUAGACUUGUGCAAAACAAGUUUCAAGUUUAUAGAUAUUAAGUUUGUAAUGUGAGCAUCAAAUGUGUAUGUAAAAAUACUUUUUACCAGUCUGGAACUUGGGAAAAUCCAGGGAAUUUGAAACAUAGAUUUUAAUGAGCUGGUAAACACAAAUCAUGUCAAUAAAGGUAGUCAGGAUAUUUUAUCCUUAGCAUUGCUUCUGCAUCCUGUGUAGGAUUCCAAUUCUUGAAUAUGUUCUUUUCAAAAUCUUAAGAAAAGAACCUUUUUUCUUUAUUAACAUCAUGUGUUUACUUUCAGCAAAUAUUUGUAUUACUGCUUGAUUCUGUGACAGUCACAAUAGAUGUAGAGAAGGCAUUAUUUUUCAUUAAUAAAUGUGAAAUUGGAAUGGA